AGAGCGAGGUGGUGAGGAGAGCUGGUUGCGUGAGUCUCCUCAGCUCUGCUUACCGGUGCGACUAGCGGCAGCGACGCGGCUAAAAGCGAAGGGGCGAGUGCGAGUCCCCUGAGCUGUACGAACGCGGUCGCCAUGGACCGCCCAGAUGAGGGGCCUCCGGCCAAGACCCGCCGCCUGAGCAGCUCCGAGUCUCCACAGCGCGACCCGCCCCCGCCGCCGCCGCCGCCGCCGCUCCUCCGACUGCCGCUGCCUCCACCCCAGCAGCGCCCGAGGCUCCAGGAGGAAACGGAGGCGGCACAGGUGCUGGCCGAUAUGAGGGGGGUGGGACUGGGCCCCGCGCUGCCCCCGCCGCCUCCCUAUGUCAUUCUCGAGGAGGGGGGGAUCCGCGCAUACUUCACGCUCGGUGCUGAGUGUCCCGGCUGGGAUUCUACCAUCGAGUCGGGGUAUGGGGAGGCGCCCCCGCCCACGGAGAGCCUGGAAGCACUCCCCACUCCUGAGGCCUCGGGGGGGAGCCUGGAAAUCGAUUUUCAGGUUGUACAGUCGAGCAGUUUUGGUGGAGAGGGGGCCCUAGAAACCUGUAGCGCAGUGGGGUGGGCGCCCCAGAGGUUAGUUGACCCGAAGAGCAAGGAAGAGGCGAUCAUCAUAGUGGAGGAUGAGGAUGAGGAUGAGCGGGAGAGUAUGAGGAGCAGCAGGAGGCGGCGGCGGCGGCGGAGGAGGAAGCAGAGGAAGGUGAAGAGGGAAAGCAGAGAGAGAAAUGCCGAGAGGAUGGAGAGCAUCCUGCAGGCACUGGAGGAUAUUCAGCUGGAUCUGGAGGCAGUGAACAUCAAGGCAGGCAAAGCCUUCCUGCGUCUCAAGCGCAAGUUCAUCCAGAUGCGAAGACCCUUCCUGGAGCGCAGAGACCUCAUCAUCCAGCAUAUCCCAGGCUUCUGGGUCAAAGCAUUCCUCAACCACCCCAGAAUUUCAAUUUUGAUCAACCGACGUGAUGAAGACAUUUUCCGCUACUUGACCAAUCUGCAGGUCAGGCCAGAGAGACAUUUUUUAGUAGGAUCGGGCACGAAUCUGGUUCUUGGAGGUGACGGGAGGUGGGUGGGAAGGGCCGUGGUGUGUUGGGGGGGGGACAGAUUCCACCAUCACCCCCACCUGGAGCAGGUACAGGAUCUCAGACAUAUCUCCAUGGGCUACAAAAUGAAGCUGUACUUCCAGACUAACCCCUACUUCACAAACAUGGUGAUUGUCAAGGAGUUCCAGCGCAACCGCUCAGGCCGGCUGGUGUCUCACUCAACCCCAAUCCGCUGGCACCGGGGCCAGGAACCCCAGGCCCGUCGUCACGGGAACCAGGAUGCGAGCCACAGCUUUUUCAGCUGGUUCUCAAACCAUAGCCUCCCAGAGGCUGACAGGAUUGCUGAGAUUAUCAAGAAUGAUCUGUGGGUUAACCCUCUACGCUACUACCUGAGAGAAAGGGGCUCCAGGAUAAAGAGAAAGAAGCAAGAAAUGAAGAAACGUAAAACCAGGGGCAGAUGUGAGGUGGUGAUCAUGGAAGACGCCCCUGACUAUUAUGCAGUGGAAGACAUUUUCAGCGAGAUCUCAGACAUUGAUGAGACAAUUCAUGACAUCAAGAUCUCUGACUUCAUGGAGACCACCGACUACUUCGAGACCACUGACAAUGAGAUAACUGACAUCAAUGAGAACAUCUGCGACAGCGAGAAUCCUGACCACAAUGAGGUCCCCAACAACGAGACCACUGAUAACAACGAGAGUGCUGAUGACCACGAAACCACUGACAACAAUGAGAGUGCAGAUGACAACAACGAGAAUCCUGAAGACAAUAACAAGAACACUGAUGACAACGAAGAGAACCCUAACAACAACGAGAACACUUACGGCAACAACUUCUUCAAAGGUGGCUUCUGGGGCAGCCAUGGCAACAACCAGGACAGCAGCGACAGUGACAAUGAAGCAGAUGAGGCCAGUGAUGAUGAAGAUAAUGAUGGCAACGAAGGUGACAAUGAGGGCAGUGAUGAUGAUGGCAAUGAAGGUGACAAUGAAGGCAGCGAUGAUGACGACAGAGACAUUGAGUACUAUGAGAAAGUUAUUGAAGACUUUGACAAGGAUCAGGCUGACUACGAGGACGUGAUAGAGAUCAUCUCAGACGAAUCAGUGGAAGAAGAGGGCAUUGAGGAAGGUGAGCUAAUCCCCCCCCACCCUUGUCUUCCCUCUUUUCUUUUCUCAGAGCAAGCCUGGCCAAGGACAGGGUAUCAAGGCAUGAACACAAUCUGCUUUUAUGGAGGAAAGAAAAAGCAUUCUGAGCAACUUUUUAAACAAAGGAAGUCCAGUGAACAUUUAACUUAAAAAUGUAACAAAACCCCAAAAAAUCAUUUUAGUUCUAGGUGAUGGAUAGAUGGUUGUAACAGCAGAAGAUGAAGAGUACACAGAGAUAGGAGACAGUGGGUGGAAAACUGAAAAGGACACUUCACAUCGAGGUGGGGGAGUGGCAAAACACAGUGCAUUUCAGCACAGUCUGUACCCGGCCUUGGCCUUUGGCGCAUUUCCAGGCUUGUGUUGGGAGCAGAGCAUGAAGUGAACAGUGUGCUCUCUGAGUCCAGAAAAGGGUGCAGCCAGUUCUACCUCAAGAAUCGGGGUGGGGGGGGUGGCGGGGGAAGAGCUAGAGGAAAAAGGUGACAUUUGAACUGGAGGAUGCAUUCACACUGAGGAGCUUUAUGGAGCAUUCUCCGUGGAGUGGAUCAUCUGAACAAGGACCUGGAAGGGUGAAAAUGCAUCGUAGGUUGGGCAGGGUUUCCAAAAUUAUGUCCUGAGGAUCACUCACCAGAUCUGAAAGCUGCUUCCCACAAAAGGUUUCAGUGGUCGUAUAUGUUGGACAAGUACUGCAUAUAGUAAUACCCUCUUGUAGAGUCACAUUAGCACCUUAAAGGCUCUGAGAAUAACACGAGAAUUAUAAAGGUGCUGAGAAGUACUCAGAUGGGAGGUGGAAGGGGCAGGAAAAUCAACUACUCUUCGGGUUUUUUUGGCUAUGGGGUCCCUGGCAAACUUCCAUUGAGGGCAAGGCCAGGGCACUAAGGGAAGAGGAAUGAAUGUGGAGCCUCAAUCUAGACAUGUUCAGGUAGGAGAGAGAAACAGGGAUUCUCAGUUCUCUUCCCCUCCCACCUGAUGGCAUCUCUUUUCUCAGAAGGGGAGGCAGAGCUAUCUGCCCAGCCCUGAGGGUGGGAGUGGGGGUGGGGAAUUGGGUUGCAGAACACAAACUAGGGCCUCUUUGGAUCAGACUGGGGGAGAAAGCGAGGAAGCUGCCUGGAGAUGAAUAGGUUUAUUCAGCUGAGGUCAGAGCUCAGGAAGAGACACACAUUGAGGAGUACAAGGGGGAGAAAAAGCUACUAUCAGAGAUGUAUCAGUUUUGACAGAGGCAGGGAUCCCACACUGCCUUCCUGCCUCCCUCCAUCUCCCUCUCAUUCUGUGGGCUUGCUUGAGUACACCCACACACACUCUUGGCUGUUUGUUCCAAGCAGAGGCGCUGACAAGUUGUCCCAGGCCGCUAAAAACCCUGGCUAUGGUCUCUGUUCCCUUUUAGAGUGACACCUAUCUGCUCAUCUAACUGCCUUCCUCCAUUUCCCCUUCCUUGCUUCUCCC